AAAUAAGAUCCAGCCCAUCCACCAAGACCCAAGGCCUGGAGCAUCUCCUUACCCUCAAGAAAGGACCUCUGGAUGCAUCUGGAUUGGAUCAUGCGGAUGCAGGUGGUAAUGAGGAUGGUGAUGGUGGUGCUCCUGGUGAUGGGUGUCAUGGUGAUGGUGGUGGUGCUGCUGGUAAUGUUGUCAUGGUGAUGAUGGUUGUCGUGAUAAUGGUGAUCAUUGUGAUGGUAGUGGCGGUGGUGCUCAUGAUGGUGCUGCUGGUGAUGGUGGUGAUGAUGGUUGUCAUAAUGAUGGUGAUAAUGGUGAUCAUUGUGAUGGUAGUGGCGGUGAUGCUGCUGGUGAUGGGGGUGCUCAUGGUGAUGGUGGUGCUCAUGGUGUUGGUGGUGCUGCUGCUGGUGAUGGUUGUCAUGGUGAUGGUGGUGAUGAGGAUGGUUGUCAUAGUGAUGGUGAUAAUGGUGAUCAUUGUGAUGGUAGUGGUGGUGGUGCUGAUGGUGAUGGUGGUGCUGCUGCUGGUGAUGGUUGUCAUGGUGAUGGUGAUGAGGAUGGUUGUCAUAGUGUUGGUGAUAAUGGUGAUCAUGGUGAUGGUAGUGGUGGUGGUGCUGAUGGUGAUGGUGGUGCUCAUGGUGAUGGUGGUGGUGCUGCUGGUGAUGGUGGUGGUGAUGGUGAUCAUUGUGAUGGUAGUGGCGGUGGUGCCCAUGGUGAUGGUGAUGGUGAUGGUGUUGAUAGCUACGGUGAUAACAUCAGUGGUGGUCAUGGCAGCUGUCAUUUACUGACCACCUCCUAUGGUGAGUAAAAGUGUUUUCCAUGUUGCUUUGCCAUCACAACACAUCCCUGUGAGGAAAUAUUAUCUCCCAUAUUAUCUCCACAGUGGAGGGAACAGAGACUAGAGUUGUUUUUCUUUUUUCUUCAUUUUUUUUUUUCUUUUGAGAGAUGGGUCUUGUUUUCUUGCCCAGGGUGGAGCUCGGUGAUGCAAUCAUGGCUCAAUGCAACUUCCAACUCCUGGGUUCCAGCGAUCCUCCUGGUUCAGCCUCCCAUAAGUGGGACUGCAAACGUGAGCCACCACACCCAGUUAAUUUUUUUGUUAGAGACAGGGUCUCACUGUUGCCUAGGCUGGGCCUUGACUUCUUCAUGUAUCAUGAGCUAGAGCUUGCAAGUGUUGGCCUUGCUACUUGGUGGCAAAUCAGACCCUGUGAGUUGCAGUUUCCUCUUUAGUAAAAUGGAGGUAGUGAAAGUCCUCUCUGUUCUGACAAGAGGUUCAGGUGUGCAACAGUAAAAUUUUAAUGAAUAAAUAGUGGGUGUGGAAGUUUGUAAAUGAUAAAUUUACAUUUAUUUACAAACUGUAAAUGAUAUUGCUGUUAGAUUAUGUUCUUAAAGACAAGAUGCUUGUGUGUGUUUAAAGCAGGAGCAAAAAGUUUUCGAAGUCCUAGUCACUGAAGUCGAUACCCCAGCAGUGAAGUUCCUUGUGUUCCUGGAGGAUGCCCUGCUGACAACCCCCUGCAGAGUUAACAGGAUAACAGAAAACCCACAGGGUUGCCAACAUCACUUUUAAAGACCUUGACACUCAGGUAGCAUUUUCCAGGGGCUAGUACCUCCUGUUGCUUUUGCAGAGUCUUUGUGACAUCACUUGAUAGGUCUGACAAAUCUCAGGUCAGGCCCAGGGUGCCGUCCGUUCCUCUUCUGCAGGGCUUGUAGUUGUGUUGGCCACCAGCGGGAAAUGCCGAGGUUCUGGAAGGAAAUAACAGGAAUAGAAAACAGUCCUAAUGUGACUUUUCUUGAAAAAUAAAGCUUUCCAUGAAAUAACAGGAUAAGCAGUCCUAUCACCUUACAAAUUAAAUUAAUAACUUACAGAGCAGGAUUGAAAUACAAAUAAGCAUGUAUGUCACGCACUUUCAUUCUCAUGCUGAGCAGGUGUUUAACUCUCAGAUGUGCCUCCAGCUACGGCAUUGCCAGGCUUUGCACAGGGGCCCUCAGAGCCAGCCCCUUGACUGCACCUGAAUCCCCGAGCUCUGUUCACCUGCGGAAGCCUGGUGCCUCCCCAUACCUGGGGAAUCCACCACUGGGUCCAGGAGUCUGUGUGUAACAUGCUUCCCACAAGAUUCGGGAUCCCCUGAAGUUUGAGAACCAAGGCUCUGGGUAAGGUUAACCUUUUCCCUGGCCACCUGACCAGAUGGAAAGAUGUGAAGGUCAUGCUUCUUCAGCUCUUACUGGCCCUUUUGUGGUGGUGAUGAUGAUGAUGAUGGUGGUGGUGGUGGUGGUGAUGGUGAUGAUGAUGGUGGUGGUAAUGAGGGUGGUGAUGGUGAUGGUGGUGGUGAUGAUGGUGGUAGUGGUGGUGAUGAUGGUGGUUGUGAUGGUGAUGAUGGUGGUGAUGGUGGUGAUGAUGAUGGUGAUCAUGAUGAUGGUGAUGGUGGUUAUGGUGGUGAUGAUGGUGAUGAUGAUGGUGAUGGUGGUGGUGAUGGUGAUGAUGAUGAUAGUGAUGAUGGUGGUGAUGAUGCCAAUGAUGAUGGCGGUGGCUGUCAUGCCUUGCUAACCUCUGGGAAAGAUUGAGGACAUCGGCAUGUCGGAAAGGGGCCCAGCUCCAGUUCCUCAGAGUACAUGCCUUGAAUACUUGGGCAUGGAAUCUCCCCAAACUUCCCUUUUCCCACCUGCAAAAUGGAAAUAAUAUCUGUAUCAGCUAUAAAGGCUUAUGCAAAUAUUAGUGGUUUUAUUAUAAUUCAGAGGACUACCCUGGAGUUUAAUCCUCUGAGUAAAAAGCAGGAAGUAAAAACUGUAGCAGUUUGUAAACAGUCUGUGAUGUUAGAUUGUUUCCAUUUAACAUUUUAUGUGAUUGGUGUUUAGACAUUUCUCUUCAUCUGCAUUGGUUUUUCUUAGGGUAGAUUUUCAAACUUAUGUCUUUUAAAAUACUUUUAAAAAAUACAAAAAGUACAGAAGAUGAUGUGCUAAGCCUCCCUCGCCUGCCCUUUGGUGUGGUGUUUGCGACGGCCCAGGGCCCAGCUCUUCCAGGCUUGUCUGCUGAUGCCCACAGGGACCCCUCCCUGCAGUCUUUGUUCCGGUUUCCUCAGGGCCUUUGCCACUAGUGGGGGUUCAUGCUGAAGCCUCUGCCUGAGGUAGUGAGUUCCCCUGGGCCAAGUGGCUAGGGACAGCUGGACCUCCCUAAGAGCCACCAGCGGCAGCAAACAUGCCAACAUGUCUGCAGGUCAAUGGGUGAGAAGCAAGAGGAGCCCAACUCGCUUUCCCGUUUUAGGUCAUUCACUAGAUUUCCCCCGGUUUUGCCUUUUUUUUUUUUUUUUUUUGAGACAGAGUCUCGCUCUGUCGCCCAGGCUGGAGUGCAGUGGCAUGAUCUCGGCUCACUGUAACCUCCGCCUCCUGGGUUCAAGCAAUUCUCCUGCUUCAGCUUCCUGAGUAGCUGGGAUUACAGGCGCCUGCCACCAUGCCCGGCUAAUUUUUGAAUUUUUAGUGGAGACAGGGUUGGUCCGGCUGGUCUCAAACUCCUAACCUGAAGUGAUUCUCCCACCUCGGUCUCCCAAAGUGCUGGGAUUACAGGCAUGAGCCACCGCGCCCGGCCCCUUGCAUACAUCUUGGUCCAAAUCAGAUUCUGUCUUGGGGAGCAUCAUUUCAUAAUCUCUGCUGGCUUUGAACUUGUCACAGUUCAGACGUCUUCCUUCUUCUGGCUCCUCCUGGUAGCCCCAGGUGCCUCCUUCCUGACAGAGCCUGCUGCUCCCGUAAUACACACUCACCCCUAAUGAGCUACUUAAAAAUAAUCAAUGAUUUCCAGAUAAAAAUCACCAUUAAUUUUAAAUGCCCUCUGUAAACCUUGUUACAAAUAAUUGCCAGAAACACACAAAGUCUGAAAUUAAUUAAAAUCGACAGCCUCAUUUGACGGGAGUUGAGCUUCUGGCUUCUUGGUUAUGUGCGUCUCUUGCUUGGGCAGAAGCAGUGGCUGCGAGAUGUGAGCCCAUGGGGGAGUUUGCUUAGGACCCGCCGAGCACUUGGGCCUGUGGAGGAGUGGGGAGGACACGGGCUUAGAGUCCUGCAGACUUGGCUGGCUGGCCUGUGCCCUCUUAGGGUAAUCGGAUGACUUUCCGAGCCCCAGGUUUCUCAUCUGUGGAAGGGUUUGGUAGUGCCAGCUCCCCAGGGUUGCACGUAGGUGAUGGCAAGGGUGUGCCUGCCCCAAGUGGAUGCUCAGUCAUGAUCUUGUCGUCUUUCCUCUUCUCUCUCCCUGCCCCAGAUCAGCCUUUGCAAAGUACUCAUACUGGGUCAUUCACUCACUCAUUCACUCCUGCAGUGAGAUACACAGAAGCUGAUAGGCAGCAGAGGCGGCAGGGACACCGGGUUCCCCUCAUCUGAAAAAAAAACACUGAGGCUGAGAAUGGAGAAGUGACUUAGUCUGGGCCAGUCCUGGCAGAACCAGGAGAGAACCUGUGUGCCAUGACCCCCUAGCCCAGCGCUGUUUCCACCGCCACACCCCCGUUCCCUCGGGGCUGGUGGGUGAUGGGGAAACCGCAUUUGCCAAGGCAACGGGAGGCAGCCGAGGGCUGGGGCUGGGAAGUCCUGCAACCCCCUGGCCCUAGGGUGGCACGAGCCCCUUUCUCAGCAGUGGGGUACGUGUGCAGGCACCAGCCAGUUCUUCAGCUGGGUUGCCAUAGUAACUGGAUACACUUUUGUUACCUUCUUUUCAUGGUCAACCUUUUGUCAGUUUCCAUUCCAGAACUCUGAGAGUCAUCCCAGCGUGUCCUUGAGCAGAACACCUGCGUGCCGCUGUAGCUUGUCACAUUUCUUUGUUGGUCCCCGUGUAGCUGUUGUUAAGGGGCACAGAAAAGCCAGUGUCCCCUCCCUCCCCUCCUUUCUGAGAGAGCACAGGUGAAGGGCUUGUCCAGCCAGGAACGAAUUCUCAGGUCCACUCUUCACUGAUGCACAAAUGCUAGGCAGUCACUUAGCAUCUCUGAGUCUUGGUUUCCUCAUCUGCAGAAUCAGGAAAGUCACAUUUCCCUGAUCAUUAGCCUGUUCAUUGAGCCAGGGCUUCCUGAGCACCUGCUGCCUGCCAGGCCUUGGGUGAGGUGCUGGGUUCAUGACAGCACAGGGUCCCCACCUUCAAGACCAUAGCCAGAUCUGCAGACAGAUCAGUAAACUCCAACUUGGUGAGUGAGGCGGGGAGUGCAGAGGUCUGAGGGGGUCACGAGAAGGAGCUACCAGCCCAGCCAGGGGCUGCUGGAGACAGUAUCCGAGGAGGGUAGAGAUGACACAGGGAAAGUGUUGAACAGAUCAUGCCGCUCAGUUAGGGCAGUUUCUUGCCUCCUCCUCCCUCUCCCUCCCAGUCUCUAGGUCUCUCCUCUCCUCCCCUCUGUCUCCCUCUUUCUCCAACCUGAUGGGAAGCUUUGGACAUAAAGGCCGUUUCCUCAUCAGACUUCUUCUAUGCCUUUGGUCCCAGAGACACGGCAACCCCCACGCCCUACCCUAAGUCUCUGCAGACAGCAGCUCCGGAGAAGAGAACAAAGCUUGGGACUUAUUUAUUUCCCGUUUUGCAGAAAUGUUUAUUUGAAAGCAGCACAGCAAGGUGGAAUGGUUUGAUUUGAUUAGCAAGUCUAAAUGUAUUAGCAGCAAGACAGAAACGAUAUUACAAUUAGCAGUAAUUAGCUGUGUGAUGACUCUGGGCGGCAGUGCUGGGUGACAGAUGCUGCUUCCUGGUCCCGGGUUAGACGGAGAGGGCAUGUUACCCUUGUGAAGGGGCUCGGCUUCCUGGGGCGGGCAGAGGACCCUGGCCUUGUUUUCAAGGCUGAGUGACAGCUAAUUGUCCCUUGGAAGAGACACAGGUGUCAGCACCCACUUGUGUUGUGUGGAAAGUGACUUUGCGGUCUUGGGGGAGGCAGUGGCUUGACUUGUAUGGAUUUGGAAGCUUCGCAGCUGCCCUGAAUUUGCCUCUGAUGGCAGUGGCUUCCUUCGUACCACUCAUCCCUUUUCCAAUCUUUAUCACACACAGCUCCUCCAGACCCCCUUCACUGGGUUUUACUUAUGGGCUGGCUCUGUCCCUGAGAUGUGGCCUGUGCUGCAUCCCUGGGCCUCCAAGGUCUGCAGUGUGGACGCCCUGUGUGGUGAUGCCCGGUAACCCUGCAGGGUGCUGGACAUACACUCAGGAGACUCUGGGAACCGUGUGUCCACAUCGCUACAUGUUACCUACUUCAGCGUGGGUGAGCAGUGACUGCAAGCCAGUCUGAGGUGUAGAUAGAGACACCUGAGACCCUGAACCUGUCCUCCAGGAGUCCAGAUCUUCCACUGGGGGCCAGACAUGCUGACAUCCUGCAGAAAGAAACCAGUGCUCCUUUUGGAGUGGUGAAAAUGUCCUGGAACUUGGCAGGGGUGGUGGUUGCACAGCUUCGCAAAUGGAGUAAAUGCAGUGGCCUCGUAGGCUUUGAAAUGGUUACUUCUUCUUUCCUUUUUUUUUUUUUUUUUUUUUUUUUUUUGAGACGAAGUCUUGCUCUGUUGCCCAGGCUGGAGUGCAGUGGCGUGAUCUUAGCUCACUGUAGCCUCUGUCUCCCGGGUUCAAGCGAUUCUCCUGCCUCAGCCUCCCGAGUAGCUGGGACUACAGGCACCCGCCAUGAUGCCUGGCUAAAUUUUGAAUUUUUAGUAGAGACCGGGUUUCACCAUGUCGGCCAGACUGGUCUUGAACUCCUGACCUCAAAUGAUCCCCCUGCCUCAGCCUCCCAAAGUGCUAGGAUUACAGAAGUGAAAUGGUUACUUUUAUAUUAUGUCAAUGGUUUUACCUCAAUGAACAAAAACAAGCAAGACAACAAGACAUUUUGAAAGCCCAAACACCAUAAACUGGGCACAGCUUAAAGUGUCUGAGCACACACAGCCGGUAAAUGGAGAUAGUCAUGGACACCAAGUCUCCCUCUGAGCAGGGAAGGAGCUGGAGGAGCCAAGAGGGGAGAGGCACAGCUGCCACGGCGCUGGGCACGUCACAGGCCAGAGUUGGAGAAGGCUGGGGAGGACACUGGGCAGACAUGAGACAACCUUUCCUUUCUGCCACUGGCUGCCCUCCAGGGGCUGCAGGAAGGGGUCAGGGUCUGCCUUCCUAUGGCUGGGAGGGGGCUGGCAGUCCUGCAGCCCCGCCUGUCCUUAAGACUGCCUCCUGAGUGCCCUUGCACGACCUCGGGUGCCUGUCAGAGACCACGACAGCCUCUGGAGUGUUGGCUGCUCUUUCCCUGGUGUCACACGUGAACUUGGCCUUGGCCACUGUGUUCAUCAGGCCGCCAAUACCAAAGGACCAGGGCUGCUCAGAGAGGCAGCCCCCAGAUGGCACCUCCUCCCUGUACCCCACUGCCCCCAAGCCAGCAGGAGGAUCCUCCACACUCUAGAUCUCUGCCAAGCACUGUGGGUGCAGGAGAGAAUGAACCAGAUGUGGUCUACCCUUAGGGGGCUGCAGCUGGAGCUGCCUGAGCCACGUGGCAGCGAGGUCUAGGGGUGCUGGAAAGGGACAAAGCUGGAAGAAAUGUUUUCUGAGCCCAAAGUGCAGUUUCAUUGCAGGGGGUGGUUGUUACUGGGGGUGAGGCUGUGAACUGGGAAGAUGCCCUGUCCUGCGUUUUCUCCCCGGGGCCAGUGGGCCUGCCUCACCUGGGAUCUCCAGAUGCAGCAGCUGCACGCAGAGUCUACACAGCAGUGGCCACCUGGUUCCCCUGUGGACACAUCCUUUGUUCCUCAGAAUGAAACCAUCUUGUCAACAGCCUUCGCCUAUGGGAGCCAGGAGAUUGGUUAGCUCCUACGGGAGCCAGGAGAUUGGGCAGGUGUAGUAGAAGAGGAAAAAAGGGCGGUCAUUCUACAAUUGGGAGGAUGCCUUACCCGAAUCAGAGAAAUGCUGAUGAAAACCACAGGGAGGCUGGGCGUGGUGGCUCACGCCUGUAAUCCCAGCACUUUGGGAGACCGAGGCGGGUGGAUCACUUGAGGUCAGGAGUUUGAGACCAGCCUGACCAACAUGGAGAAACCCUGUCUCUAUGAAAAUACAAAAAUUAGCCAGGUGUGGUGGCGCAUGCUUAUAGUCCCAGCUACUUAGGAGGUUGAAGCAGGAGAAUCGCUUGAACCCGGGAAGCGGAGGUGGCAGUGAGCCUAGAUCGCGCCACUGCACUCCAGCCUGGGCAUCGCAGGGAGUCUCCAUCUCAAAAAACAAACAAAACAAACAAAAACAAAAUCACAGGGAGAGUCCUUUUUGUUUCUUCCAGACGAAUACCAACACUGAAGGAGAAUGAUGACGGUGUUGGGGGCUCCUGGGUGUGAGGAGUGCUGCUGGGUGGGAAGUGGGAGAAUUUGGAAAACAAUUCGGAAACAUCUAGUAAAGAUGAGGGGAGAUGUACAUCUCCUGCAAACCGGAGAUCCCACUUGUAGGUAUUUCCCAUAGAGAAAUUAUUACACACGUGUCCUGGGAGGCCUGAAAAUCCUAGCAGCCAAAAUGAAAUACAACAGAAUGUGGCCACCACUGAUGGAUAAUGGAUAAAUAUGCACAUGUAUGCACUGUGUCUACAGCAAGGAAAAGGAAUGAGUGAGGCCACGUGCAACAACCUUGACUCUUGGGAGCUUGGAGUUGAAGUUUUCUUCAAAAAGUUGCAGAAGAAAACUUCAUAUGAUUUCAUUUAAUUAAAGUUCAAAACAUGCAGGCCAGGUGCAGUGGCUCACACCUGUAAUCACACACUUUGGGAGGCCAUGGUGGGAGGAUUACUUGAGGCCAGGAGUUCGAGAUCAGCCUGGGCAACAUGGUAAAACUCCAUCUCUACAAAAAAAAAAAAAAAUGAAAAAUGAGCUGGGUGUGGUGGCAUGCACCUGUAGCCCCAGCUACUCUAGAGGCUGAGGUGAGAAGAUCGCCUGAGCCCAGGAGGUUGAGGCUGCAGUGAGCCAUGAUUAUGCCACUGCACUCCAGCCUGGGUGACAGAGCAAGAUCCCAUCCCAAAAAACAAGCGAUAUCCUUUUUUUUUUUUUUGAGACACAGUCUCGCUCUGUCACCCAGGUUGGAGUGUAGAGGUAUGAUCGCAUCUCACUGCAACCUCCGCCUCUCAGGUUCAAGUGAUUCUCCUGCCUCAGCCUCCCAAGUAGCUGGGCUUACAGGCGCACACAACCACACCUGGCUAAUUUUUGUAUUUUUAGUAAAGAUGGGGUUUCACCAUGUUGGCCAGGCUGGUCUCAAACUCCUGACCUCUGGUGAUCUGCCCACCUCGGCCUCCCAAAGUGCUGGGAUUACAGGUGUGAGCCACCACCGUGCCUGGCCUGAUACACUUUUUGAUAUACAUAUGUGGUAAACUAUUAAAAAAAAAGUCUGGGAAUGAAAAAUACAAAAUAGUAGUAGUUACCUGUAGCGAGUGGAGGAUUUCAAAGUGAAUAUUUAUUUUAUUUUUUCCUUUCUUCGUUUUUUUCUUUCUUUUCUUUUUGAGACAGGGUGUCAUUCUGUCAUCCAGGCUGGAGUGCAGUGACAUGAUCACAGCUCACUGCAGCCUCACCCUCUCGGGCCCAGGUCAGCCUCCCUAGUAUUAAUAGCAGGGACUACAGGAGUGUGCCACCUUUUUUGCAUCUUUUGUAGACACAGGGUUUUGCCAUGUUGCCCAGGCUGGUCUUGAACUGCUGGGCUCAAGCGGUCCUCACACCUGGGCCUCCUAAAGUGCUGGGACUGCAUUGUGAGCCCCCGCCCGGCCCUGGCCACUUUCUUAACCCGAGUGCUAUGUACAUGGAUGCUUCUGGUAUUAUUCUUCAAAUGUUACACGUUUUAGAACCUUUAAUCUCUCUUCAGUACUUAAUAAAACAUCUGUAUGUUUUUAAAUGGGCCUGUAGGUGUGGGGCUUCCUGCCUCAAAUGUGAAAUUCUGUGCUUUAGUACAGGCAGAUGGGUCUGGGCUGUCCUUGGACAUACAAGGACCUCCAGGGACAGGACACUUCCAGCUCCCCAGAGGCUGCAACUUGUAUAACUUGCAGAAACAAGACGGAACAGUCAAAAGUGCAUGAAACCAACUGUGUAAAUUGUGAAAUGUGAAUUGUAAUUUUGCUUUUUUCCUUCUAAAAUGGCAUGAAGUCCACAUUUUAAAAGUUUGGAUAGGGAAAGAUUGGUCAAUGGGUACAAAGUUACAGUUAGGUGGGAGGAAUAGUUCUGGUGUUCCAUUGCACAGCAGGGUGACUGUUGUGCUAACAAUAUGGUAUUAUGUAUCUUAAGACAGUGUGAAGAGAGGAUUUUGAGUGUUCUCACCACAAAGAAAUAAUAAAUGUAUGAGGCGAUGGAUAUGCUAAAUACCUUGAUUUGAUGAUUACACAAUAUGUACAUGCAUCAAAAUAUCCUACUGUACCCCAUGAAUAUGUAGUUAUGUGUCAAUUAAAAACAAAAUGUUUUCUUGAGACAGGGUCUUGCUCUGUCGCCCAGGCUAGAGUGCAGUGGCGCAAUCAUGACCCACUGCAGCCUCAGCCUCCUGGGCUCGGGUGAUCCUCCCACCUCAGCCUCCUGAGUAGCUGGGACUACAGGUGUGCACCACCAUGCCAGGCCAAAUUUUUUGAAUUUUUUUGUAGAGAUGAGGUUUCGCCAUGUUGCCCAGGCUGGUCUCGAACUCUUGAACUCAAGCAAUCCGUCUGCCUUGGCCUCCCAAAAUGCUGGGAAUUACAGGCGUGAGCCACUGUGCCCAACCCAAAAUUUUUAAAAUAGGUUUUCUUUUUAACCAAGGUAAAUUCUGGAAAUGAAGCAAAACUGACCAGCGCCCUCUCCUGGGCGAGUUGGAAGUGGAGCCCUGGGUGGGAGGACCCGCUGGCCCCAAGAGCCCUGCUGGUUCAGCACCACGGACAGCACUCAGGGCAGCCUCUUUACUGGGCGUGGCCGUGGGCUUCCCUCGCUGAUUUGGCCGCAGCUUUGGGGAGGAAGGUGGCAGGAGCCUGGGUUCCCUCCUGCCUUCCUCGUAGGCUGAGAUGAGCUGGAAGAAGCUCAUGCCACAGUGCGCAGCAUAGCUCGGUGUUCUGUAAAUGCUUAGAAAACCCUCUCUGCUGUCAGGGCAGGAGGGCGCCCAGUGAUGAGACCUGCUUGCGACUCAUGAGGGGACUCCAUGUGCAGUACCGAUGUCACCAGGCCUAGAGGGACGCCUGCUCUCCAUACACUUUCUAGGCUGGCUGGAGGGAGGGGAGGGACAGGGGCCUCUUAUGGCUCUGUGAGACACCCACCCAAAGGCGCUUCCUGCUCCGGAAGGAACAGUGUCACGGUGGCCAGAGGGGGAGUCCAAGGCCAGGCAGGUGCUGGUCACUCCUUGGGCUCAUCCCAGGCGUGGGGCUGGCUGAGGGAGCUGAAGUGUCUCAGCCAGGAGCUUGGACCCUUGAUUCUGCUUCCCUGGAGAAAAGGUGGGUUUGAUGGAGAAGGGGUGAGAGGAGGAUGGUGAUGGGGGCUUCAGGAAGAUUCUCUGCUCUCUUCCCUCAGCCAAGGGUGCAGAUUGGGGAGCAGGUGGAGAGAGAGGAGAAGGUGGGGUCAGCGUCCAGGACAGGCUGUGGCUCCAUGCUGGAGGAGAGACAGAGACCGACAGGAGGAUGUCUGAGGAUUCUUUCAGCUUUGAAUUGUAGGAUGUUUGUUUCUCAUCACAACACCCAUGUGUUAAUUCACAUUUCAUUUUGAUCUGCUUGUUCAAUGAUUGGGUACUGAGUGGUAUUAAUAUGAUCAGAAUUUUCAAUAACAGAGAAUAUUACGCUAUUCAUUGAAACAAAUUGGUUGGCAUCUAUAUCUCCAUAUACCACCCUGGUCUUAUUAGAUCUAAAUCAUAUUCACGCUCAGCGCUCUGAUUUGAACUGUAAACCCAGCAUGGGAGGCGGGAUACCUGCUGUUUGAAGAGCUCUCUUUCUCCUCCAAUUUCUGGUCUGAUUGGACACACACUGUAUAGCACCAGGCUGCAUCUAUGAGCAGGUCAGGUGGUGACGAGGGCCCGGAAGUGACCCGCUGUGGUCACAGUGGAUUUGCCUAGUGUUAAAACUCAAUGUAAGCUGCACGGAUGUAGGACUUUGUGCAGGGUGGUACCAACACAUGUGGGUAUGUCGGCUGUUUGGGUGAAAAUGUAAGCAUGUGUCAUGUCAGGGUGUGUUUGUGCAGACCUCUGUGUCCUUAAGCAUAUGCAUUUUUUUUUUUUUUUUUAAGACAGGGUCUCUGUCGCCCAGGCUGGAGUGCAGUGGUGCGAUCAUGGCUCACUGCAGUCUCAACCUCCUGGCCUCAAGUGACCCUCCUGCCUCAGCCUCCCGAGUAGCUGGGACUACAGGCAUCCGCCACCAUGCCCAGCUGAUUUUUAUAUUUUAGUAGAGACAGGGUUUCGCCAUGUUGGUCAGGCUGGUCUCGAACUCCUGGCCCUCAAGUGAUCCACCUGCCUCGGCCUCCCAAAGUGUUGGGAUUACAGACGUGAGCCACCGCACCUGGCCGCAUAUGCACGUUUACAGCAUCACACACAAACACUCCAGGCAGAGAAUGGAACUGAUAGUCACGCCUGUCUGCUGUGGCCUCAGCCCAAAGCUUUUAGUACUUCUGAGCAAGGAGGAGUGUCAGCCUGGCCAGGGUGUCUCACUGGUGUCCAAAAACUACGCCCCUAGUGUUGUUUCUGCUAAUUCUGCCUACAUUGUCCUUACCUGCCUCCUCUUCUGGCUUAUUCCUGCUAAUUUGUUAAGAAUUGACUUGGCACCACCUCCUCCAAGAAGUCUUCCCUGACUUCCCAGUGCUGGGCUAGGUCUUGUUCAGCUAGUUGCAUAGCUUCUGGGGACAAGAGCCACACUUUCCUCUCCCAUGGCGACCCCACCCUUACACUGUCUUGAGAAAGCUGGGAAUACAGUGGGUACUCUGUAUAUGUUAGUUGUGUUUCAGAAUGGUUCCUUUUCCCCUCACCCCAGUCAAGCACAGUGGGAUUUUUCUCCAGUAUUCACUUGGAGACCCUGGUGGGGUUUCUGAAGGUAAGCCUUAUAAAAGUGUGCCCCCCACCCCACGCUGAGCCCCUAGGUUUUAAGUCUUGAGGUAGCCCCCACUCAGCUUGAGCAGUUCGCUGAAGUUGCCUUUUUGUUCCUCCCAGUUCCUGGCUCCAGCAGCCUGUCCUCACUGUGAGCUGUGGUUCUCUGUCUCCGCCUGUCUCUUUAGUUUUAGGGUUGGCUGUUUGUCCUGUAACCUCAAUUUUCUGAGGAUUCUAAGAAAAGUCACUGAUUUUCAGUUUGCUUAACUUUUUUCUGGUUUCAGGGGUGGGAGCUGACAUCUGCCAAUCUGGAAGUUGAUGUGCAUAGGUUGAGUGCACUUGAAUCUUCUCUUUGCUUCUUUGGCGGACCCAGGGUCCAGGGACAGGGAGGGGACAGGGUGGAGACCAGCAGACCCCGUUUUCUCUGACUGGGGCCUGAGGACCUGAAGGGAAUGCAGCCCCUCGGGGACUUCUGUAUUAAACACAGACACACAGACUCCACCGGGCUGUGAUGACUGGGGGUGGGGAGUCAGUCAUAGUGUUUGCACUUAAUUCUGACAACAAAGCUGAGGGUCAUCAGAGCCCGGAGUGGGAGUUUGUUAAAGUGACAGUCACCUGGUGUCAUUCUCACAGCUGAGGACCUCCUGCAUGGCGGGGAGGGUGUGCCUCCUCAUCUCUGAGCGCCCUGCCUGCCAACCUCCCUCCCCCGCCCCUACUUCCUUGGCCUACUUGGGCCUUGGCACCAGGCCUGUGCCAGGGCCCAAGUUGUCUGGCAGCAAAGACACAGUCCCUGUCUGUAGGGGGACGGACACACAGCUCCUUUGCACACAGCUUUGGGACAGGGAGAGGGGCAGAAUCCUAUUUGUCCUAGGAGAAGCUCAGCUCCACCUGGGUGGGACAUGCAGCAGGUGCUCAGUGUUUGUUGACUGACUGAGUGAGGGCUUUCAAGGACCCACACGAUGUCCGCUUCUGCCCAGAGCACCCUGAGCCGACGUACAUGAGGAGUUUCCACUGAGGAGCCAUGUCAGGGCGUGCAGUGUGGGCCUGGAGAGCCAGCACCGGCUUCCUGGUUCCACUGAGCAGCCGCGUCCGCCAACACUCGGUUUCCGGCUUCCUCAUUGCACUGAGCAGCCGCGUCUGCCAACACUCGGUUUUCGGCUUCCUCGUUCCACUGAGCAGCAGCGUCCGCCAACACUUGGUUUCAAGCUUCUUUGGCUUUUCAGGUUUUUUCCCCUCUUAACAAAAUGAUGAAAAUGCACAACAGGCCGAAAUGCCCAAAUCCGUCACUCAUGAUACAUUUUACCAAAGUCAAAAGAAAAAAGAAACGUCCUCCUUAAUCACCUUUCAUAUUUUCAUUAGCAACAUCAAAGCGAUCAGGUCUGGGAAAGCCCAUCUGAGUCAUGUCUCUGGUAAGAAGUUGAUGAAGAAUACAAAGGAACUUGAAUUUCAAAGCCAAGCCUUUAUCUCUCAUUCAUGUUUUCUACUGUGAGGGCUCCCCCAAGACCCAGCCCUGUCAUUCAUUAGGGGAGGGCCUGCAGGUCUGAGCAGACACAGUGUUGCCCACCCUAAAGCAUUCAGUGCAGCCGGUAUGGGUGACCCUGUCCUGAGCCCACUGGAACCCUCAUCUCUCCCCCCAACUGCAACCCAGGGAUAGGAGUUGCUUAACCUCCCUGAGCCUGUUUUCUUAUGUGUUUAUUAGCAGCUGUGGGGCGCCUGCUUCAUGCCUUACUUUGUGCUGGACCAGGUGGUAUGCAAGGAACGACAGACAUGUCCGUAAGGAGCUUGAGGCUGAGCUUGGGAGACAGACGCAGCAAGUGCGGGAGGGGUCAGUGCAAAGCCAUGUCAGGGCAUGCAGUGACCCAGAGGAGAGAUUGGCUCUACCAGGCACACCCACGAGGGCUCCCUGGAGGUGGAGGCACAGUGUGUUUUGAUGGCUUGUGGGAGGGCUAAGUUUUCUGGGAAGGGAGAGAGAGAGCCGCCCAAGGGCCAGGCCCUGUUGUCUCAGCAGCCCCAAGGCACUGGAAGCCCUGGAGUGGAUGGUGGUGUUGGGGAAUUCAGGCUUCUGCAGGUACCCGGGAGAGCAAAGGGUGGACACAGUGGAAAUUGGUCCCAAGUCACCCAAAGUCCAAGAGUGGAAAGUGGAGACCCCUUCUCAGUAUCUCCCCAACUCUGUGUGCGGUACAGGUGGUCUCGGAUGCACUCCUUCUGCUGCCUACCCCGAAUGGCCCUGAGGAGGGCUGUUUACCAGGCACCAAUGCUUUAUCAUCUGAAAAACACAUGGCAGAAAGAAUUCAAGGGAGGACGGAGAAAACCCAAAGAUACCUUGUCAGGUGAGAGGAGGGCUUCAGAGUCACUCACGCCAAACAGGCUUCAUAGCCACGCCAGGGGCCCAUGAUGGUGAUCUACAGGGUCCAGCCGUGAGUGAGGAGCCCUGUGGUUGAAAAACACAGGGUGUGGGUGGAUUAGAACUCCUUCCAAAACACAGAUUAUUGAGCCUUUCCUCCCAGGGUUUUAGAUUUAAUCACUCUUGGGUGGGCCUGAGAAUUUGCAUUUUGAGGCGAGUCCUCAUGCUCUGCUGGUACUGCUGGAAUGGCCACCACACCUUGAGCACCGCUGGGUUGGAGGAGGAGUGCUGACGGAGUGCUAAGCUGAUCUCAUCCUGGCCAGACCUUAGGAGGUGAGUGGUUUCAUUUUACAGAUGAAGAAAUAGAGGCAAAACAGACGAAGAGCCACCCCCCAUUUUCUGCUAGUCAGAAUGUAAUCAGCAUGCAGAUUGAAGGAAGUCUUAGACUGUGUCCCUCGCCACUUGUCCCCCAAAUCUUUCCUGGCUGUAUAGUCUCCAAAGAGCUUAGAGUUAAAUUUGGGGCAAAGAGGGAACCCUGAGAAGUGAGGCUGGAGGGGGCAGGACCAUGGUUCUCUGUGGCUGGACUGGAUGAGCAGUGCUAGAGCAGUUCGGCGAGCUUUGACCACACGGACCCACCUUGACCCUGAACCCAGGUUUCUAAGGAGGGCCGAGAAUUGGCCUAGGAAUUGCUGCUGUUGAAGGUAGGCAGGUGUGGGGAGGGUCAUGCUGGCCUUGGUACCACUGCUGAGGUGGUUAAGGGGAGACCCUGGGGAGCCACUGGUGGCUCUGUAGCAGCAGACCUAGAGGGGUGGGCAUGGGGCUGCCGCCUGGCACACCCAGCCCUACCAGGUCCCACCCUCCCCUGGCACAGGUGCUGCCUUUGGUGGUGCAGCUGUGCUUGACCAGCAUCUGCCCAGUGGCUUUGCAGAAUGAACUAGGAAUUCCUGGAAUCUCGAGCCUAUAAAAAUAGUGUGCAGAAAAGAUUCCCCCCUGCCCUUCUGUGCAGAGCAGGUCACAUGGCAUGGCCAGCCUGGCUUCAAGGGAUGGGGAAUAUGCCUCCCUUCAGGACGCUUUUAAUCUUUCUUCCUAGUGGAAAGCUUACUGGCCUGGGAUCGAGGCAGGAGUGCCAUGCAUCUCCGAUAAGCCAGCUCUGUGGCCUUGGGCUGGCCGCACAGCCUCCCUGGGCUCUGGCUUCCCCGAGUGCCAGUGCUAGCGUGGAGCUGUGAUCUUGGUUGACCACCUGUAGAGUUGACCACCUGUAGUUUCAUGAAGUGGCUGCGCUGCUGGAGGAUGUGAUGAUGAUAGAGUCAAGAGCUUGAAGGUUGUCCAGAGCGCAUGGAAAAACGAGACAGUGUUCAAAUCUCAGCCCUUAGUAGCUGGAUGUCCUUGGGCCAGUUACUUAACCUCUCUGUUCCUCCAUUUCCUCAUCUGUAAAAUGGGACACUAUAGGCCCUUAUAGAAUAGUGGCAAGGAUCAGGUGAGAUAGCGGAAAGUCUACACUCAGCCAUGCAUGUCAUAUGCUGAGCCAGCUGGGCCCCCAGGCUUUCACGCACCUCAUCUGCAAUCCUCAAAUGGCUCCAUUUUUCUUUUUCUUUUUCUUUUUUUUUGAGACUGAGUCUCGCUGUAUGACCCAGGCUGGAGUGCAGUGGCGUGAUCUCAGCUCACUGUAACCUCUACCUCCCAGGUUCAAGUGAUUCUCAUCCCUCAGCCUCCCGAGUAGCUGGGAUUACAGGUGCCCACCACCACGCCUGGCUAAUUUUUGUAUUUUUAGUAGAGACGGAGUUUCACCAUGUUGGCCAGGCUGGUCUUGGGCUCCUGACCUCAAGUGAUCCGCCCGCCUUGGCCUCCCAAAGUGCUGGAAUUAUAGGUGCGAGCCACCGUGCCCGGCCGGCUCCAUUUUUCAGUUGCAGAAAUGGAGGCCUAGGAGUUGAACCCCACACCCUCCUGACUCCACAGCUCAAGCGCCUUUCCAGGCCUCAGUCUAAGAGCUUGAGGGUGGAAGAACGAGGCAGCUUGCAGCAGCUGGCUUUGGGGUGUCCUUUGUGAUGAAAACACCCCUCCUUUUAGGGAGCUCCUGCAAACUGAUGCCAGCAGGGCCAGGCGAGCAUGGAUCACGUGGACACGGAGGCCCUUUGUCCUGCUUCGUCCGUCCAACCCUAUGCCAGUGAGCUCCACGAAGCAGUGACGCCUGCAGAGACUCUGGCCACAGGAAGUGUCAGUAUCCUUUGGUGCAGCUGUGAAUGGUGCCCAGGAGCUGAGCGUCUUGUAGUGCCUGAAGGCUUUGGGAACGAUCACUGCAGUGCCUGUCACGGGUCCUCAGGUCAGCUCCUUGCAGAGGUUGGCCGGGCAAGGAGCGGCAGUGCUACCUCAGGUUAGGCCAAAGACUCUGAUUCCAGACAGCCUCCCCGUUGCCCCGGGCCGGGACCGGCCACCCAAGCAGCCCCCAACAUUCCAGAAGGCCACCGUGGUCAGCGUCAAGAACCCCAGCCCAGCCCUCCCCACCGCCAACAACACUGUCAGCCAUGUGCCAGCGCCCGGCAGCCAGCCCCAGGCCCUCGCCGAGCCCGCCGCCCUCGCCUCUCCGCUGAGCAGUGCGGGGGUGGCCUACGCCAUCAUCUCCACCUCCCCCAGCAAUGCCGCCGCCAUGGCCCCCAGCACCGCCGUGUCUGUGGUCAGUGACAGCAUCAAAGUCCAGCCCCUCCUCAUCAGUGCUGACAACAAGGUCAUCAUCAUUCAGCCUCAAGUGCAGACGCAGCCCGAGAGCACGGCAGAGUCGCGGCCGCCCACAGAGGAGCCAUCUCAGGGAGCUCAGGCCACCAAAAAGAAGAAGGAAGACCGGCCCCCGACCCAGGAGAACCCCGAGAAAAUCGCCUUCAUGGUAGCGCUAGGCCUGGUUACCACGGAACAUUUGGAAGAAAUCCAGAGCAAGCGACAGGAGCGGAAGAGAAGAAGCACAGCCAACCCUGCCUACAGCGGCCUCCUGGAGACCGAGAGGAAACGGCUGGCCUCCAACUAUCUCAACAACCCCCUGUUCCUCACAGCGAGAGCCAAUGAGGACCCCUGCUGGAAGAACGAGAUCACCCACGAUGAGCACUGUGCCGCCUGCAAGCGAGGGGCCAACCUGCAGCCCUGCGGCACCUGCCCGGGGGCCUACCACCUCAGCUGCCUGGAGCCGCCCCUCAAGACGGCGCCCAAGGGCGUGUGGGUGUGCCCCAGGUGCCAGCAGAAGGCCUUAAAGAAAGACGAGGGUGUGCCCUGGACUGGGAUGCUGGCCAUCGUGCACUCUUAUGUCACCCACAAGACAGUCAAAGAAGAGGAGAAGCAGAAGCUGCUGCAACGAGGCAGUGAGCUGCAGAACGAGCACCAGCAGCUGGAGGAGCGGGACCGGCGGCUGGCGUCAGCAGUGCAGAAAUGCCUGGAGUUGAAGACAAGCCUGCUGGCCCGCCAGAGGGGCACCCAGUCAUCCCUGGACCGCCUGCGGGCCCUCCUGAGACUGAUACAGGGCGAGCAGCUGCUCCAGGUCACCAUGACGACCACUAGCCCUGCCCCACUGCUGGCCGGGCCCUGGACCAAGCCCUCAGUGGCAGCCACACACCCCACCGUCCAGCACCCCCAGGGCCACAACUGACCCCGAGGGACCAGUCUUCAUACCCACGGAAAGUUAUUGGGACCCUGCUUACACAGCCUGGGGGUUCUGUCGGCCUUAAUUCAUAAACACUAUGAAUUUCAGACAAAAAUUAACCAGACAGAGGAGAGGAGGGAGGAAGAGCUGGGCGAGAGGCCUAGAGCCAGGACCAGGUGGGGGUGCGGCCCUGUGCCCUCCAAAUUCACAGGGGGUACCUAGGAGCCAGGUGGGGUACGACAGGCUGGGGCACACAGUCUCCCCCCGGCCACCUCGGGGCUGCCUGGGCCUCUGGCUUCCAGGCCCUGCUCUCCACGGCCUCCCUCUGGCCCGUUGGAGGGGCAGGCUGAGGCUGUGGAGGGGACAAGCACGCCCCCCAGAACGCAGUCUCCACUGAGGGCACCGCCUAUUGGUGUCCUGUGGGAGGGCGAGCUGAGAACACAUGGACUAGCUGAGUGGUAGCGGUAGUUGGGACGAGAAGCGGGGUAGUGGAUCUAGGUAGUUCCUCAAUGCCCCACGCUCCUAGGAGGUCCCCCUGGGGUGGGCGGGCGGGCCUGGGGCACUCCGUCGCCUUUGCAGAACCACCUGGGCCCCUUUCUGUCAGUAUUAUUAGGGUUACGAAUUGCAGCUGUUUAACUUGAAAGACACUGUCGGAGGUGAGCAUCUGGGCGCCGGGACGCUGCAGUGAUCCCCGCCAGAGCCUGUGCCCUUCCUGCUCCGUCUUUGGGGUCCUCAAGGCUGCCUCCUUCCUUUUGCCAAUCUCUUGGACUCAGUUUGCCGUUGAUGCGUUUUUCUCAUGGAGUUUCUGGGCAGAGUGGAGCUGCAACCCUGUUGUGGGGGGCAGCAUUUGGCAGGUUUUCUCCUUGGGGUUGAAUCAUUCAACUUAACGACUGAAGCCCUUUCUUGUCUCCUUUGGAAGAGCCGAUAAGUAUUCCACUCCUCCCUUCUUGCCAGUGCAGACACUAUGCCAAAAAAUAACUUCACACUUUUGUAUGGCGUUUUUAUUGUGAGAUAUUUAAUGUGAAUGGUUGGGGGGACUCUGGCUGACUUCCUUUCUGCUUCUAGUAGUCUCUGCUUCAAGGUACAAAUGGGAACACCUCCCCUCGGGAAGCCUGGCCAAGCUGGAAGAUCCGGCAGGUUUUUUACGAGCCGGGUGGAGGGUUGGGGAGGAAAGAAAGGGCGGUGGCUCGGGAGGUUCCGGCCUUCGGGGACCAGACUUGCUGCCAAGGGCUUCUGCAUCCAGGGUGGGCAGUGGCAGCUUGUCACCCUUGCCCGAUUCCCACAUCCCAGUCCUGAGGGACUCAGCACAACAGGAUAAGCGUCCAGGAGCCACGGGCUCCCACCCCGAGCAUAUCACAUGGUGCCGAAUUGCACUGAACACGCGUGUGUGCAUCGCACGCGGCCACGACCACAGACACGCAUGCACACACGCAGAGGUGCAGAGCGAGGAGGCCGGCAAAUCCCGCAGCUGCCACGGUCCCUCCUGUCAUUCUCACGACUCCGGGAGAAACUGUGCUGUAUGAUACAGAUCUAUUUUAAUACACUUACCACUGGGUGAACAAGAUUUUUAUAUUCUUUUAUUGAUGAACAAAGUGAACCGUGUGAGGCACACGUCUUCUAUAUUGGCUACUCUGUGCCAAGUAUGCAUUACCGCGUGGCUUGCGAUGUCCAUGUCUUCAGCUUCCUUUUCUGUUGGUUUGGUUUUCUUCGCGGAUGGAUUGAGUUACAUGUUUUAACAGUGUAAUGGGAGGAUCUGAAAGGUUGGACCCGGGAGGGGUAGCUGCCGAUGUGUCUUGAGAUUGUUAGGUUUUUUUUGGACCAAGGAGGACCGUCCAGUGGGUAGUGAGGAUAGAGAAAAAGUGUUUGUCUUAAAUACGCCAAUGUAGUUUUCCUUCUUUACAAUGUAUUAAACUCGAUCGAUGAUUUCAAA